UUCGAAUACAGUAGCAGCACAAGGCCGAUAACUAGCCCUUUACAAGAAGUCCACUUUCUGGUAUAUACAAAUGACGAUGAAGGCUGUCAGGUAUGGUUACAUAUCCCAUCUGGUUAAUUCUGGCAAGUGAACCCAAGCGCAUUCAGAUGUUUUUAUAGAUCUAGGAAUAACCGUGUUUUCUAAUCCUGUGCCUAUAAGUGAUGGUUGCUAAUGGGAGGUUGUCAUAUGACUUAACUAUGAGCCAACACUGAUAACUCAUGUUCCUAGACAGUUCAUCAAGAGACAAGCUAAUCUGUAAUAAAUACAUUCUUAGAAAGAAGUGGAAAGUUAUUGGCAUAAAAAUGGCCUAGACAUUUUAACACUGACUACAUGAAAGCUAAGUCAUGGCUUUAUCUAUGGGGAAAGGGCAGAAUGAGAGAAGCCUCAAGGAUUUAGUUAUUUGGAUAGCAUAGACCAGUCUACACAAGUCUGUGAGUGUCUACAAACUAGAAAUAGCAGCACCAUAUUCAGCAGUGGAGAAGCAGUCAAGGCACACUAACUAAGUAGUUCCCACUGACAUUAGAAGAAUGGUAUACUUAGGUUUAAUCUCAGUUUUGCCAUUUAAAAGUUGGGUGACAUACCUCUCUGAAUCUCAGCUUUUUUUUUUUUUUUUUUUUUUUUUGAGACAGAGUCUCGUUCUGUUACCCAGGCUGGAGUGCAGUGGUGUGAUCUCGGCUCACUGCAGCGGCGUGAUCUCAGCUCAAUGCAGCCUCCGCCUCCUGGGCUCAAGCAAUCCUCCCAUCUUAGCCUCCCUAGUAGCUGGGAUUACAGGCAUGUGCUACCACGCUCGGCUAAUUUUUGUAUUAUUAGUAGAGAUGGGGUUUCUCCAUGUUGGCCAGGCUGGUCCUGACCUCAGGUGAUCCACCCACCUCAGCCUCCCAAAGUGCUGGGAUUACAGGCGUGAGCCACUGUGCCCAGCCUGAAUCUCAGUUUUAUCAAGUGUAAGAUGAGUGUGGUAAUAACACCUUUCGGAAUUGUUCUAACUAUUAAAACGGGUGUAUUUGAAGUGUUUUGCAUGAUAUCUAGCACAUAGAAAACCCCCAAAACUGGUAGUAGUCAUUACCCAACUUUAAGGACUGACAAGCAAUUGCUACAACUUACUAACAUCACCACUUAAACUGGAUCAAAGAUAAUUUUGUUUUUUAAGUUCUUAGUUAUACUUACCCAUUCUGGAUGGAAGUGUGGUCUUUCCAGAGAUGUUUCCCAGAGUUCCCCAGAAACACUCCAAAGUAUUGCAUGAUGUAGUUUGUAAGCAAAUUUAUCCAUAGGAAAUAAUAAUAAUAUUUUAAAAAACAACAUUUACCCCCAAAGGUUCUUAGUUUUUUUCCCCCGGUAAAUAUAAAAUAUCCAGAGACAUAUUUUUUUGCUCAAAGAUAAACUGGGGGAAAUUAUUAUUAGCAAACUGUUCGUGAUAUCUGUGUCCUUGUUGAGUUCACAAUAACAUCUGCCCUUUAUUGGGGUGACAUCUUCAGUAGCAAUCUGGAAAGUAACUGCCCCAAAUUUCAUUGUUAACCAAGAAUUAGAAACAUGGACUGGUGCAGUGGCUCACGCCUAUAAUCCCAGCACUUUGGGAGGCUGAGGCAGGGGGAUUGCUUGAGUCCAGGAGUUCAAAACCAGCCUGUGCCACAUGGCAAAACCUCAUCUCUACAAAAAAUACAAAAAAUUAGCCGGGCGUGGUGGUGUACAUCUGUAGUCCCAGCUACUUGGGAGGCUGAGGUGGGAGGAUCAGUUGAGUCCAGGGGGUUGAGGCUGCAGUGAGUCAAGAUCAUGCCACUGCACUCCAGCCUGGGCAACAGAAUGAGACUCUGUCUGCAAAAAAAAAAAAAAAAGAAAAGAAAAGAAAAGAAAGAAAGAAAGAGAAAAAGAAAAAGUAGAAACAGUCCCAAAGAUACCUGAAAAGAAAGAAAAUGGAUGAAGACAACCCAAGUGAAACUUUAUAACUCUACUCUGUCGCCCAUUGCUCAAUUUUAUCACUCACACGACCAAAAUGCCUUUUUGUUUUUUCCAUUUCUAAACAAAACUUCAAUGUCUGAGGUUUUCUAACGUGGAUUUUCGUGUUUUCAUUCAGGAGGCUUUGGCUGGACCUAAGAGAUGAAGCAUACUGCAUUUUUAGAUGAAUUCACUAACUGGUCAAGAAUAAAUCCCAACAAGGCCAGGAUUCCCAUGGCAGGAGAUACCCAAGGUGUGGUCGGGACUGUCUCUAAGCCUUGUUUCACAGCAUAUGAAAUGAAAAUCGGUGCAAUUACUUUUCAGGUUGCUACUGGAGAUAUAGCCACUGAACAGGUAGAUGUUAUUGUAAACUCAACAGCAAGGACAUUUAAUCGGAAAUCAGGUGUGUCAAGAGCUAUUUUAGAAGGUGCUGGACAAGCUGUGGAAAGUGAAUGUGCUGUACUAGCUGCACAGCCUCACAGAGAUUUUAUAAUUACACCAGGUGGAUGCUUAAAGUGCAAAAUAAUAAUUCAUGUUCCUGGGGGAAAAGAUGUCAGGAAAACGGUCACCAGUGUUCUAGAAGAGUGUGAACAGAGGAAGUACACAUCGGUUUCCCUUCCAGCCAUUGGAACAGGAAAUGCCGGAAAAAACCCUAUCACAGUUGCUGAUAACAUAAUCGAUGCUAUUGUAGACUUCUCAUCACAACAUUCCACCCCAUCAUUAAAAACAGUUAAAGUUGUCAUUUUUCAACCUGAGCUGCUAAAUAUAUUCUACGACAGCAUGAAAAAAAGAGACCUCUCUGCAUCACUGAACUUUCAGUCCACAUUCUCCAUGACUACAUGUAAUCUUCCUGAACACUGGACUGACAUGAAUCAUCAGCUGUUUUGCAUGGUCCAGCUAGAGCCAGGACAAUCAGAAUAUAAUACCAUAAAGGACAAGUUCACCCGAACUUGUUCUUCCUACGCAAUAGAGAAGAUUGAGAGGAUACAGAAUGCAUUUCUCUGGCAGAGCUACCAGGUAAAGAAAAGGCAAAUGGAUAUCAAGAAUGACCAUAAGAAUAAUGAGAGACUCCUCUUCCAUGGGACAGAUGCAGACUCAGUGCCAUAUGUCAAUCAGCACGGCUUUAAUAGAAGUUGUGCUGGGAAAAAUGCUGUAUCCUAUGGAAAAGGAACCUAUUUUGCUGUGGAUGCCAGUUAUUCUGCCAAGGACACCUACUCCAAGCCAGACAGCAAUGGGAGAAAGCACAUGUACGUUGUGCGAGUACUUACUGGAGUCUUCACAAAGGGACGUGCAGGAUUAGUCACCCCUCCACCCAAGAAUCCUCACAAUCCCACAGAUCUCUUUGACUCAGUGACAAACAAUACACGAUCUCCAAAGCUAUUUGUGGUAUUCUUUGAUAAUCAGGCUUACCCAGAAUAUCUCAUAACUUUCACGGCUUAAAAAUAUUUUUAUCAUCAAAGAGAUGAUUUAAGUCAUCUGUAAGAACAACAUGCAAUCUUUGUCUUUGCUUCUGGCCUGUGUAAGCAGAUGAAAGUUUCCCUUUUAGGUGCCAAAAUGCUGAAAAUUACCUUUUUAAAGUGCUCUAUUGCUGCGAUUUGUAGCAUACCUUUUUUUCUCAGCAAAUUGAUGGGUGGAAGCUGAGAAAUGUAUGGUAAAUGUCACAGAGCUACAACCAUUCACAGACACCAAAUCUCUAGGAGAAUAAAAAGCACAUUAUUCUUUUUCUAUCAGAAAAAAACAAGAUGCAUCACCUUAAAACCAAGAUGACAUUGUUCUUCUUGGAACAUGUUAAGACAUCGAAUGGUGGCGGGUUAAACUGUACUGCUUAAGUGGAGCGGCUACCGUUAUGCAUCUAUCACAGUUGGGGAUUUUGCCUUAUUAAGGAAAACUUGUCAAUAGUUCAGCUGAAAUGACUGAAUCACAGAAUAUUAACUCUGUUAUGGAACAAAUCAUAACAGAUUUUACCUGUUUACAUUUCAGGUAAAAAUGUAUCGCAUUGUUAUCUAAUAUUAAAAAAUUACCCCCAAUUUUAGUGACUUAAUCCCACACAGUCUUUAUGGGUCAGGAAUUCAGGCAUGGCUUACCUGGAUCAUUCUGCUAGGGUCUCUCUGAAGUUACAGACAAGAUGUCAGGGGAUGUGGUCGUUUGAAGGCUUGUCUGGGCUGGAGGUCUAUUUCCAAGGUGAAUCACUCACAUACCUGGCACGUUUCUGUCAGGUAUUGGCAGUCCUCAGUUCCUCUCCUCUCAGGCCUCUCCACAGGCUGCUUGAGUGUCCUCAUGACACAACAGUUGGCUUACUCCAGAGUGAGCAACUCAAGAGAGAGCAAGGCAGAAGCUACCAAAUCUUUAUGUUUGAAGUCAUGCACCAUCUUUUCCACGAGUAUCCUGUUGAUUAUUUUGAUCAGCUUGUUCAGUCUGGGAGGGAAUUGCACAAGGGCAUGAAUACUCCACUGGCAAGGAUCAUUGGGGGCCAUCUUGGAAGCUGUGUGAAUGAGCAAAUGAAUGCACAGAUAGAAUAUUAGCAGUGACAAUGAUGCUAGAGGUCACCUACCCCACUGUCCUCUUGUCCUUCUCCCCCAACCCUCCCCUGCUCCCAGGCAAGAAGCCCUCUAGCCUCUGCUUGAUCACUUUCAGCACUCAACAUCUUCAGGGAACCUAUUCCGCCGUGGGACAGUGUUAAUUAGUGGAAAACUCUUUUUCAAAAGUUGAAAUCAGUUCCUCUGUGUCUAUUACCUGCUGAUCACUGUCCAGACUUCUGGAGGACACAGAGCAAGUUUUAUUCCUCUUACUGAUGGUAGCCUUUCAGAUCCAUCCCUUCCCUCCAGUAUAUUAGAGUUACGUAAAUUCUUAAAAUGCUUAGCAGCUCAUUUAUCCUGAAGCAUCACUUUUGAAGAGUUACAGACAUUUAAGAAGUAUUUACAUUAUCAUAAAUAAAUUACAUGCGCAUUUAAAGAGAACAGAAAAGUAUAAAGAAAAAUAACUCACCAAACUCACUCAUAAUUCCAGCACUAAGGGAAAACCACUGCCAAUUUCUCAUGUCUCCCUUCCAGUUUCUUCUCUGUCCAAAUUCAACAAAGUCAAAAUCACAUUUUGUUCUGUCACAAAUCAUAUAAUAUUAUUUCUACCAUUUUUCUUUUUUUAAUCUUUUUUUAUUAUACUUUAAGUUUUAGGGUACAUGUGCACAAUGUGCAGUUUAGUUACAUAUGUAAACAUGUGCCAUGUUGGUGUGCUGCACCCAGUAACUCAUCAUUUAGCAUUAGGUAUAUCUCCAAAUGCUAUCCCUCUCCCCUCUCCCCACCCCACAACAGGCCCCGGUGUGUGAUGUUCCCCUUCCUGUGUCCAUGUGUUCUCAUUGUUCAAUUCCCACCUGUGAGUGAGAACAUGUGGUGUUUGGUUUUUUGUCCUUGCGAUAGUUUGCUGAGAAUGAUGGUUUCCAGCUUCAUCCAUGUCCCUACAAAGGACAUGAACUCAUCAUUUUUUAUGGCUGCAUAGUAUUCCAUGGUGUAUAUGUGCCACAUUUUCUUAAUCCAGUCUAUCAUUGUUGGACAUUUGGGUUGGUUCCAAGUCUUUGCUAUUGUGAAUAGUGCCGCAAUAAACAUACGUGUGCAUGUGUCUUUACAGCAGCAUGAUUUAUAAUCCUUUGGGUAUAUACCCAGUAAUGGGAUUGCUGGGUCAAAUGGUAUUUCUAGUUCUAGAUCCCCGAGGAAUCGCCACACUGACUUCCACAAUGGUUGAACUAGUUUACAGUCCCACCAACAGUGUAAAAGUGUUCCUAUUUCUCCACAUCCUCUCCAGCACCUGUUGCUUCCUAACUUUUUAAUGAUUGCCAUUCUAACGGGUGUGGGAUGGUAUCUCAUUGUUGUUUUGAUUUGCAUUUCUCUGAUGGCCAGUGAUGAUGAGCAUUUUUUCAUGUGUUUUUUGGCUGCAUAAAUGUCUUCUUUUGAGAAGUGUCCGUUCAUAUCCUUUGCCCACUUUUUGAUGGGGUUCUUUGUUUUUUUCUUGUAUAUUUGUUUGAGUUCAUUGUAGAUUCUGGAUAUUAGCCCUUUGUCAGAUGAGUAGAUUGCAAAAAUUUUCUCCCAUUCUGUAGGUUGCCUGUUCACUCUGAUGGUAGUUUCUUUUGUUGUACAGAAGCUCUUUAGUUUAAUUAGAUCCCAUAUUUCUACCAUUUUUCAUUAAACAUUACAAGUUGUUCUCUUGUGUUCUUAUUUUUUCUGUAAACAUAAUUUUAAUGGCAGAGAUAUUCUGCUUUAUAUCUUUCCCUAUUUUAUGUAUAUAGAAUUAUAAAGUUUUUAAAAAUGUAAUCAUCAUUAUUUAUAGUUUAAUAAUCAGUUUCAUCUUGCAGUGUAUCAUUUUCCUCGUCAUUAAAUAUUUUACGUAUCAUUUUUAA